GUGUCCCCACAGCCCUGUCACGAAUCCCGGUCGGGUUCUGGGAGGCACAGCCUCGGGGUUGCGGGCCGGGUGCGGCUCGGCGGUGGAGGACUCACUUCCUGCUCCAUCCCCGGCUGGGCCCUGGGGCGGAACUGAUGACGCUUGAUAAUGUGGCUGGGGACUUCAGGGAAGAGUGGGUUACCUGGACACUGCUUAGAGAAUCCUCUCCAGGAAUGCCACCCAGCACAGUUAGAAGAAUGGGCUCUCAAAGGAAUUUCCAGGCCUAGUGUAAUCUCCCAGCCGGAGCAGAAAGAAGAGCCAUGGGUCCUACCACUCCAAAACUUUGAGGCGAGGAAGAUCCCGAGGGAAAGCCACACAGACUGUGAGCAUCAGGUGGCAAAGCUCAAUCAGGACAAUUCUGAAACAGCAGAACAAUGUGGAACAUCCUCAGAAAGGACCAAUAAAGAUCUUUCUCAUACUCUUAGUUGGGGAGGAAACUGGGAGCAAGGCCUAGAAUUAGAAGGGCAACAUGGAACCCUUCCAGGAGAGGGCCAGCUGGAGUCCUUUUCACAGGAGAGGGAUUUAAACAAGCUCCUGGAUGGAUAUGUAGGAGAGAAGCCUAUGUGUGCAGAAUGCGGGAAAAGCUUUAACCAGAGUUCCUAUCUCAUAAGACACCUAAGAACCCACACUGGCGAGAGGCCCUAUACGUGCAUUGAGUGUGGGAAAGGCUUCAAACAGAGCUCAGACCUUGUCACCCAUCGCAGAACACACACAGGAGAGAAGCCCUACCAAUGCAAGGGGUGUGAGAAGAAAUUCAGCGACAGCUCAACACUCAUCAAACAUCAGAGAACCCACACAGGGGAGAGACCCUAUGAGUGCCCAGAGUGUGGAAAGACUUUUGGGCGGAAGCCACACCUCAUAAUGCACCAAAGAACCCACACAGGCGAGAAGCCCUACGCGUGCCUGGAAUGUCACAAAAGCUUCAGUCGAAGCUCAAAUUUCAUCACUCACCAGAGGACCCACACAGGGGUGAAGCCUUACAGGUGUAAUGACUGUGGGGAGAGUUUUAGCCAGAGCUCGGAUUUGAUUAAGCACCAACGAACCCACACGGGAGAACGGCCCUUCAAAUGCCCGGAGUGCGGGAAGGGCUUCAGAGAUAGUUCUCAUUUUGUAGCUCACAUGAGCACUCAUUCAGGAGAGAGGCCUUUCAGUUGUCCUGACUGCCACAAAAGCUUCAGUCAGAGCUCACAUUUGGUCACGCACCAAAGAACACACACAGGUGAGAGACCUUUUAAGUGCGAAAACUGUGGGAAAGGAUUCGCCGACAGCUCCGCCCUCAUUAAGCACCAACGAAUCCACACCGGAGAAAGACCCUACAAAUGUGGAGAGUGUGGGAAGAGCUUCAAUCAGAGCUCCCACUUUAUUACCCAUCAGCGAAUCCACUUAGGAGACAGGCCCUAUCGAUGUCCUGAGUGUGGCAAGACCUUCAAUCAGCGUUCCCAUUUCCUCACACACCAGAGAACGCAUACAGGAGAAAAACCUUUCCACUGUAGUAAAUGUAACAAGAGCUUCCGUCAGAAAGCGCAUCUUUUAUGCCAUCAAAACACCCAUUUGAUUUAGGAAGUAGUCUUUGGUGUUCAGCUGCUCCCUUGCACAUUUUCAUUGCUACUGUCUUCAAGCACCCCAAAUAGAGAAAACCUGGGCGUCAGUGGCUCAAUUUGGGCCCUGAUCUAUUCUCCCUCUUUCUUGUCUAUGUUAUAACAGAGAGGAUAAACUUAAAGGGUCCAAAUAACGGUCCGAAUACAAAAGGCAUUCCUUCAGUGUGUGACUGACUCUUAGGGAAAUGUGAGUUUAAUAGUUGAUGCCCGCCAGGCGUGGUGGCUCACCCCUGUAAUCCCAGCACUUUUGGGAGGCCAAGGUGGGUGGAUCACUUGAGGUCAGGAGUUGAGACCAGCCUGGUGAGCAUGGUGAAACCUCAUCUCUACUAAAAAUGCAAAAAUUAGCUGGGCAUGGUGGCACGUGCCUGUAGUCCCAGCUACUCGGGAGGCCGAGGCAGAAGAAUCAUUUGAACUCAGAAGGUGCAGGUUGCAGUGAGUUGAGAUCAUGCCACUGCACUCCAGCCUGGGCAACAGAGAGAGACUCUGUCUCCAAAAAAAUUAAAAAGUUGAUGCCUAGUUACUAAAUGAGAAGUGAGAAAAAUGUGGCCUAGAGAUCACAUGUUCACCACCUAGUACAGUGCCUGGCACAACAUAGAUGCUCAAUAACUAAAUGGUCCCAUCAUUAUUAAUGAUUAAUAGUUGAGGUCUUAUAUAAAGGCUUUAAUGCAGUACCUGGCCCUUAAAAGACACUCAGUACAAGAUUGGUGGCUUUUAUCAGUCUUAUUACUCAAUUAGAAAUUUAUUAGUGUAGUCCCCCCGCCCCAAACUCAGAACGUGAAAGAAAUUAGAUUGGAACUAGAAGGUUUGGGGUUGGAAUACACAAAUUGAAUAAAAUGGAAAUGCACUGCCAGUUCAGUGCUGUGCAGGCAUUAGUCACCAGAGGUCUCACUGCCAUGACAAGGCCAAAUUAUCGUAGAGGAUGUUUGCGGUCUUGUGACUUGGAGGCUGAAAGAAUUUCAGAAGCUCUUUUAAAUGGCAGUGUAUGGCAGUGUAUCUACCAGAGGUUUGCUGUCAUCUGACACAGAGAAAAUAUCCUACAAUGAACAAGCCAGAGGGACCUGGUAGAGGACUAUAAAAUUGUGGAAGCAAAAUUGCUGAGAAUGUCAAAUGAUAUUACAGGGAUCCUCCCUGGCAUUUAGCUGAAGGAAGCAACUCUUGUUUUCUAAUUUGCUGGGUCAUUGGCCAUUUAGUUUUAGGUUAAUAUAAUUCUCUGAUCCUUUUAGGGCCAUCCAGGUUAUGCACUAGUACAUUCCUACAUUCAAUUGAAAUAAAUUGAGGGACGGCAAGUGUGUUGGAAAGAACACCGACUUCAUUGAGAAGGUAAAGUAUUUGAGUCCUGGCCCUGACGCUUAAUUUGGCCAGACUUUCAUCUUCUCCCAGCCUCAAGUUUUACCUACCUCACAAGGUUGUUGUGAGGAUCUAAAAAUACACACACACACACACACACACACACACACACACACACUUUGUUGGUUAACUAUAAAUGUAAUAUCUCUAUGUUAUAAUUCUGUUGCUAAUGUCUUUUU